GCACUCCCUCCGCGGCCGCUGAGCCGAGCGGACGCCCCCGGGGGCCGCGUCGCAGCCCUCCGUGCUCCCCCCUAUCAUGCCCGGUGCCCAGGCUGGGGCCGCCCAAGCAGCCAGGACACCAUGCCCGAGGACGGCGCUGGCGACGGCGGGGAGGUGCCCGCGCUCAUCCCGGACGGCGAGCCGCUGCGGGAAGAGCAGCGGCCCCUGAAACAGUCCCUGGGAAGCUCCCUGUGCCGCGAGUCGCACUGGAAGUGCCUGCUCCUCACGCUGCUCAUCCACGCCUGCGGGGCCGUGGUGGCCUGGUGUCGCCUGGCCACAGUGCCGCGGCUGGUCCUGGGGCCCGAGGCCGCCUUGGCCCGGGGAGCCGGGGGCCCGCCACCGACCUACCCGGCCAGCCCCUGCUCCGAUGGCUACCUGUACAUCCCGCUGGCCUUCGUCUCCCUCCUCUACCUCCUCUACCUGGCUGAGUGCUGGCACUGUCACGUGCGGUCCUGCCAGGCGCCACGCACCGACGCCCACACGGUGCUGGCGCUGAUCCGCCGGCUGCAGCAGGCGCCGCCGUGCGUCUGGUGGAAGGCCACCAGCUAUCACUACGUGCGGCGCACACGCCAGAUCACGCGCUACCGCAACGGCGACGCCUACACCACCACGCAGGUGUACCAUGAGCGCGCUGACAGCCGCACGGCCCGCGGCGAGUUUGACUACUCGGCGCACGGCGUCCGCGACGUCUCCAAGGAGCUGGUGGGGCUGGCGGAGCACGCGGCCACGCGGCUGCGCUUCACCAAGUGCUUCAGCUUCGGCAGCGCGGAGGCCGAGGCCUCGUACCUCACGCAGCGGGCGCGCUUCUUCAGCGCCAACGAGGGCCUGGACGACUAUCUGGAGGCGCGCGAGGGCAUGCACCUGAAGGACGUAGACUUCCGCGAGUCGCUCAUGGUCUUCGCCGACCCCCGCAGCCCGCCCUGGUACGCGCGCGCCUGGGUCUUCUGGCUCGUGUCGGCGGCCACGCUGUCGUGGCCCCUGCGCGUCGUGGCCGCCUAUGGCACGGCUCACGUGCACUACCAGGUGGAGAAGCUCUUUGGCGCCAGCUCGCCCCCGCCGGGGGCCGUGCCCAGCGGGCCCCCGCUGUCCCGCGUGGCCACAGUGGACUUCACUGAGCUCGAGUGGCACAUCUGCUCCAACCGGCAGCUGGUGCCCAGCUACUCGGAGGCCGUGGUCAUGGGCGCGGGCUCGGGCGCCUACCUCAGAGGCUGCCAGCGCUGCCGCCGCUCUGUCAGCAGCAACUCGCUGCCCCCCGCCCGGCCCAGCGGGCCCCGCCUGCCCUUCAGCCGCAGCCGCCUCUCGCUGGGCGCUGGCGGCCGGGCCACGCCAGGGGUCUUCCGCAGCCUGAGCGGGGGGCCGCUGGGGCGCCGUGGAGAGGACACGGAACCCCUGGAGAGCCCGCCCUGCUAUGAGGACGCCCUCUACUUCCCGGUGCUCAUUGUCCACGGAGACAGCGGCUGCCAGGGGGAUGGGCAGGGUGCUCUCUGAGACCCCCCACGGCCCCCAGAGUGGCCCCCUCCCCACCAUUCCACCAUGGGCUUAGAUGCCCGAGUGAUUGUUGUCCAAAACAGGCGGGAAAACAGACCAGCCACACACAAGGGGCAGGGGUGAGGGUGGGGGUGGGGGUCCUUAAACAGACUAAAAUGCAGUUACCUGUGGUCAUUUUGGAGGAAGUGGAAGCCUAAGAAUCGCCCCCAGCAUGGCUUCAUCCCCCAAGAUGGCCGAUGAUCUGGCCUGAAGGCCUCUCACAAAGGGCAGGAGAAGAAGCUUCCAGAAAGGCUGGGAUGGAGGAGGAGUCCUGCGGCCAGCUGUUGCCUGCAGCAGAGGCUGCCUGUGGACACUUCCCUACCGGGGCUGAGGCCAUGCUGGGAGCCCCCCCAGUGACGCAGAAGCACAAAUUGGAGGCUUGGGGCCAUGCCCAGCCAGGUUGGCUUCCCUGGGGCUGAAGAGCUGGCUGUGGUGGCACCAUGGCCUUGGCCCUGCUACUCACCCAACAUUCCCAUCCUCCCCUGAUAGGCCCCUCCUCCUUGCCUGCCCUCUCUCCCGCUGCUCAGGGCCAGUCACUCCCCCCACAUGCAGCUACCCCUACAACCUGGGGUUCCUUCUCAGGGCCUCACCUGGUCCCCACAUCCCCUGGCCUCUGCUCCUGCCUCCCAAAGUCCAUGUCUGCCUCCAUCAGCCACACACACGCAGGGACGCCCGUUCCUUGCCCUCCCGGACUUAUCUACUCUUCACUUUCCUGAUGAUCCAUGGGGCCCAGGCCUAGAGGGCAUCCGAGGGGCUGGGCCUUGGCCACAGCCUCUUGGAUGAUGUCCUUGCUCCACCACGCAGGCCCUUGCUUCUCCCAUCAACGAGUCUUGGCCCAGGGGACACUGACCCUCCCCCAGGGAGGAGAGAGGAGUUCCUUCCCUUUCAACGAGGGCUUCCACGCCCUCUAAGGGGUGGCGGGGAAGGGAGGAGGCUGAGAAGAUGCAGAUUAAAUAAAGGUAUGGAAUGGAA